AGGGGGCGGGUGGGGAAGGAUCGCAGGCGAGAUUACGAGGCGAGGCUCGCGCGCCCGCCCCCGCCCUGGCCCCCAGUGCCCACCCGGUCGGCCCGGCACAGCCAUGAUCAAGGCGAUCCUAAUCUUCAACAACCACGGGAAGCCGCGGCUCUCCAAGUUCUACCAGCCCUACAGUGAAGAUACACAACAGCAAAUCAUCAGGGAGACUUUCCAUUUGGUAUCUAAGAGAGAUGAAAAUGUUUGUAAUUUCCUAGAAGGAGGAUUAUUAAUUGGAGGAUCUGACAACAAACUGAUUUAUAGACAUUAUGCAACGUUAUAUUUUGUCUUCUGUGUGGAUUCUUCAGAAAGUGAACUUGGCAUUUUAGAUCUAAUUCAAGUAUUUGUGGAAACAUUAGACAAAUGUUUUGAAAAUGUCUGUGAGCUGGAUUUGAUUUUCCAUGUAGACAAGGUUCACAAUAUUCUUGCAGAAAUGGUGAUGGGGGGAAUGGUAUUGGAGACAAAUAUGAAUGAGAUUGUUACACAAAUUGAUGCACAAAAUAAGCUGGAAAAAUCUGAGACCUUUAUCUUUCAGUCUCCCAGACAGGACAGGUAGACAAGCAAAUAGUUUACACUGGCCUAUUUUGUAUCAGUCAAGAUUUUUCUCAGGUAACAGCUUUAUUAUUAUUUUUAUUUUAAUUAACAAAGGUAGGAUUACAUAAGAAAAGAAAACUAAAAUUAUGAAAAGGGACCUUAAAGCUAGUGUUUCUAAUUUUAUGGACAUUGCCAUAUAUAAUCUAAUCAAAGUGGAAGAUUCGUUUUUGUUGUCUAUUUUUGUACAAAAUGAUGCCACUGAACUCAGAUGUCUUUGUUGACUUUGCUUUAUUAUAUAGCCUGAAUAAAAAGUAAUGAAAUGUAAUUGGUAUAUAAAUUAAACCUCAAAUAUGAAGGCUGUUAACGUAGGUGAGAAAAAUGAUAUGUAUGCAUUUUCUUUUAUUUGUAAGCAUAUUUUCUUUUAAAAUUAUUUCACAAAUUACAAAUGUUCCUACUAAUAGGAAAGCCAAAUAUUAUGCACUAGUGGUACUUACUGGAAAUUUUAGAAUUCAUUUAUUUAUAUUUACUACCUCUUGCAUUUAUGCUUUUCUUUCUCUAAAUUUGUAAACUGUAAGCUGAAUAUAUGUUGCUGAAUCUAUGCUAUAUGACAAAACAUUUUUAAUCGUUAUAUUUUUACUAAUGCAUCAAAGGGUUGGAAUGAUCCUCUUCGUGUAGUUUCAUCUUUAGGCAGAACUAUAUUCUUUGGAUUGAGGCUUUACUUGAAAGCCUAUUUUUUUAAUGUUCUAGAACUUUAUUAGAAAAGUUUAAAAGAGCCCUCACAAUUUAAAAAACUAAUUUUAUUGUUUUAAAAUGUUUUAAGGGUUUAUCCCUAAGAAAUUAAACAAGCACAAUCUAUUACUUGCAAUUUUUAUUUCACAGCACAUAUUGCUAAUAAAUGCCAUUUUAAAAGCAAAAGAAAAUCUAUCACAAUCGUUGCAAGAGAUAUUUAAUAAGGAAACUAAUGUAAAUCAUGCUUCAUGCUAUCUGUCAGUUAAAUCAAGAUAUAGGUGAAGAUUUAGGUUUUAUCAUGUGAAUAUUGUGUGGUAGUGCACAUUAAUUUGUAUUUAAAUCUUUACAUUGUUAUCAUUGCAUGUGUUCACUGUAUUUUUUAAUGUGUCACUGUUUUCUCUUUAUAGAUUAGUAUUUCAAAGUAACCAUUCCAUACCAAUUCAAACUACCAUCUGGUCCCUAAGCUUGUUAUAUGAAAAUCUUUUAUCAUUGUCUUCCAUUGUAAGUGUUUUAUGAUGAGCUACACCUGAGUUGUACAUUUUCUUUUUCUUUUAUUUGCUUCUGU